AGGCCCGCCCGAGUCUCCGCCGCCCGUGCCCUGCGCCCGCAACCCGAGCCGCACCCGCCGCGGACGGAGCCCAUGCGCGGGGCGAACCGCGCGCCCCCGCCCCCGCCCCGCCCCGGCCUCGGCCCCGGCCCUGGCCCCGGGGGCAGUCGCGCCUGUGAACGGUGGGGCAGGAGACCCUGUAGGAGGACCCCGGGCCGCAGGCCCCUGAGGAGCGAUGACGGAAUAUAAGCUGGUGGUGGUGGGCGCCGGCGGUGUGGGCAAGAGUGCGCUGACCAUCCAGCUGAUCCAGAACCAUUUUGUGGACGAAUACGACCCCACUAUAGAGGAUUCCUACCGGAAGCAGGUGGUCAUUGAUGGGGAGACGUGCCUGUUGGACAUCCUGGAUACCGCCGGCCAGGAGGAGUACAGCGCCAUGCGGGACCAGUACAUGCGCACCGGGGAGGGCUUCCUGUGUGUGUUUGCCAUCAACAACACCAAGUCUUUUGAGGACAUCCACCAGUACAGGGAGCAGAUCAAACGGGUGAAGGACUCGGAUGACGUGCCCAUGGUGCUGGUGGGGAACAAGUGUGACCUGGCUGCACGCACUGUGGAAUCUCGGCAGGCUCAGGACCUCGCCCGAAGCUACGGCAUCCCCUACAUCGAGACCUCGGCCAAGACCCGGCAGGGCAGCCGCUCUGGCUCUAGCUCCAGCUCCGGGACCCUCUGGGACCCCCCGGGACCCAUGUGACCCAGCGGCCCCUCGCGCUGGAGUGGAGGAUGCCUUCUACACGUUGGUGCGUGAGAUCCGGCAGCACAAGCUGCGGAAGCUGAACCCUCCUGAUGAGAGUGGCCCCGGCUGCAUGAGCUGCAAGUGUGUGCUCUCCUGACGCAGGUGAGGGGGACUCCCAGGGCGGCCGCCACGCCCACCGGAUGACCCCGGCUCCCCGCCCCUGCCGGUCUCCUGGCCUGCGGUCAGCAGCCUCCCUUGUGCCCCGCCCAGCACAAGCUCAGGACAUGGAGGUGCCGGAUGCAGGAAGGAGGUGCAGACGGAAGGAGGAGGAAGGAAGGACGGAAGCAAGGAAGGAAGGAAGGGCUGCUGGAGCCCAGUCACCCCGGGACCGUGGGCCGAGGUGACUGCAGACCCUCCCAGGGAGGCUGUGCACAGACUGUCUUGAACAUCCCAAAUGCCACCGGAACCCCAGCCCUUAGCUCCCCUCCCAGGCCUCUGUGGGCCCUUGUCGGGCACAGAUGGGAUCACAGUAAAUUAUUGGAUGGUCUUGA